AAAGAGCCCGAGAGCUUCUGGCAGCCGGCUGAGCCCCCAACGGGCCUCCCGCCCGCUGCACCUUCGCAGCCUGGCUGUGCACGCGCUGUACCUGAGACAUCCUGGCCGACUUGCAAGAACUCCAGGGAGACAGCGGAGGAGGCGAGGACCAGGAAGCGAUCGCCCAGAUUGCACUGGCAAGCGCCUUUAGAGGCGCGGUCCACUCGCCCCAACCCUGCUCGGGCGAGCACCGGAAAGCCAAUCAGAAGCCAGCUAUGCGCUAGGGGCGUGCCCAGCCCCCGCCGCGGCGCUAGCCCCGCCCGAGCCCACGUGGGACCGCUUGCGCAAACGCCGGGAGUAGCCGAAGGGGACGCCGGGAACAGGUGGGGACAACGGAAGUAGGGUGCUUAGUUUUGCUGCCGGGAGUUGGUCGAGAGUUGGGUUCAGUCCUGGCCCGUUGUGGGGACGGCACGCGGGGGAAGGGGAGGGGACGGAGACCGAAGAACGGAGGUCCUUAUGUUUCUUUUCUUUCCUUAAAUCUUGCCCGGCCUGAAGAGGCCGGAAGUUGCAUCUCUGGACAAGUAAACUCUGAGACCUGGGAAUGGCGGGCGGGACCCGCUCCUCCCUUGGGGUCUAGAGGAGACCCCCGGAGAUGGUCCCUGAUGAGCAGCGUGAUGGUGGAAAGCUGGACUGGUCUCCCGAAAGGCGAAGCCGAGGCUUCUUCCUCUGAACUUUUGGCACGUUCUUUGACUUGCUUGUGGCCGUAGUGUCAGGCCUGUAUUGCACAUUUAUGUCUGUGGUGCAUUUCUCCAUCUGGGCCAGCUGAGGGGCCCACGGACAUAGGGCACCCACAAUAGGCGUGUGUCUGCUGUGUGUUUGUGUUCGGCCGUCCUGCUUCUCUGUUUCCACACGUACACAUGCCCCUGUGUUACUUUGGUUCAUCUUCUGUACUCUGUCAGUUUUCUGCUGGUCAGAACAUCUGUGACUGUGACAGAGCUGUCCAGGAUUGCAGUGGAUAGGAAUUUCUUCACAUGGCUCCUGGAGAAGUGACCAUCACAGUUCGCCUCAUCCGUUCCUUUGAACAUCGCAAUUUCAAACCUGUAGUGUAUCACGGAGUGAAUUUGGACCAAACUGUAAAGGAAUUUAUCGUAUUUCUAAAGCAAGAUAUCCCUUUAAGGACCAACCUGCCACCACCAUUCAGAAAUUAUAAAUAUGAUGCACUAAAGAUUAUUCAUCAAGCACAUAAAUCAAAGACAAAUGAACUUGUGUUGAGUUUGGAAGAUGACGAAAGACUCCUGCUGAAAGAAGACAGCACUCUGAAAGCAGCUGGAAUCGCCAGUGAAACUGAAAUUGCAUUCUUCUGUGAAGAAGAUUAUAAGAACUACAAAGCUAAUCCCAUUUCAUCCUGGUGAAAACAUCUCGAGGGCUUCCUUUUUGCAUACCUGUAUUAAGCUCUUUAUUCCACUGCUGAAUUUUUGAAAUUGACAAACAAAUCUUAAAAAAUUAAUCCCAGGCUAUACUCUUUGAGCUAAAAUCUGGUUAUUUCUUUCUCUUCAGGUCUUUCCUUCUCUCUUUCUUUUUCUUUGUUGUUGUAAAAUAAUAUAUUAUGAGAAAAACAUUUGAUCUUUUUAAAGGGAAAUAAAUUGUUAUUAAAAAUUA